AUAAUUCGAAUACCAGGGCAGGCCGAGCCAGCCGUGCGCCGCGCUCCAGGGCCCAGGGCGCCGCACACGCACCCACCCACCCACCCAGCCUCGCAGCGCCAUGGGCAAGAACAAGCAGCCACGCGGCCAGCAGAGGCAGGGGGGCCCGCCGGCCGCGGACGCCGCUGGGCCCGACGACAUGGAGCCGAAGAAGGGCACGGGGGCCCCCAAGGAGUGCGGGGAGGAGGAGCCCCGGACCUGCUGCGGCUGCCGGUUCCCGCUGCUGCUCGCCCUGCUGCAGCUGGCCCUGGGCAUCGCCGUGACCGUGGUGGGCUUCCUCAUGGCGAGCAUCAGCUCCUCCCUGCUAGUCAGGGACACUCCAUUUUGGGCUGGGAUCAUUGUCUGCUUAGUGGCCUAUCUUGGCUUGUUUAUGCUUUGUGUCUCAUAUCAGGUUGACGAACGGACAUGUAUUCAAUUUUCUAUGAAACUGUUAUACUUUCUGCUGAGUGCCCUGGGCCUGACGGUCUGUGUGCUGGCCGUGGCCUUUGCCGCCCACCACUAUUCGCAGCUCACACAGUUUACCUGUGAGACCACACUCGACUCUUGCCAGUGCAAACUGCCCUCCUCGGAGCCGCUCAGCAGGACCUUUGUUUACCGGGAUGUGACGGACUGUACCAGCGUCACUGGCACUUUCAAACUGUUCUUACUCAUCCAGAUGAUUCUUAAUUUGGUCUGCGGCCUUGUGUGCUUGUUGGCCUGCUUUGUGAUGUGGAAACAUAGGUACCAGGUCUUCUAUGUGGGUGUCAGGAUAUGCUCCCUCACGGCUUCCGAAGGCCCCCAGCAAAAGAUCUAACAUUCUUGCUCAAAGUUGCGAGAGAAAGUAGCACAUGGAGUAGCUGAGGUUAAACAAACAAAAAAAAAUUUUAAACAAAGAAAGGAAAAAAAUUGACAAUAAAAGUCACUCUUCUAAUUGAAUAUUUUUAUAUUUUUAUGAAACAAAAGAGCAUUUCUUCAGGUUUCUAUUGUAUUUUUUUUAACAUUCUUGCAGAGAAAGCAAGAUCCAAAUUGAUUUUGGGAUAUUAAAAGUUAACAGAACACUGAACAAGGAAAGAAUGGCAUAGAUCUAUCUUUACAGUCUGGAGUUAAUUCCUGUUAACUCAUUUUAUCCAUUCCUUACAUAAUCUUCUUUCCUGUUAGUCCAGUUUGAUGGUGUGAAUGGUGAAUUUCAGGCCCAGUUGCUAAAUUUUGUGGCAUCUUCCUCUAGUCCUUCCCACCUCCAGUCAUCAGCCCCACUCUGUCUUGGAGACAGGCAGGAGGUGGGGGAAGAGCUGAAUCUCUUUAUUUUCCCUGGUAGAGACAUCUUCAAGGCAUGAAAUAGCUUAAAGAGCAGAGUAGAAACGGAAGAGGCUUUGCAAAAGGCUAGAUAACUAACAACACCUGGGUUGGGGCGGCGGCCUCUUCUCUUCAGCUCCCUUAGCUUGGCUCCGUAAGUGGAUCACUUGCCAAAUGCUUUAGAUGAUUGCCUCUCAAUAAUUGAAAGGUGGUGGUAGUUGUAUUCUAAAUGAUGUAGAAGGUUUAAAAAUAAUUACAUUAUGCUUCUAUUCUAUCAUCUAAAACAAAUCAUUAAAACUAAUUUCUAGCUAAUUGUUAAUUAUAAUUAUGCUCAGAAGUCUAUUUAAUGAGCUCUGACUGUACUUACGCUGCACUGUCGGUGUUAAGAGAAAUUACUCUCACAAGAGCAGAGGCCUGAAGAUUCUUUCUUCUGAAAGCCAAGCACCACAAGGAAAAAAAAAAUUAUUAAUAGCUCAGGUUAAAAACACCCAUUUAAACAAAAACAAGAGCAUUUGUAAUAGGAAGUGUUUAUACAAACAGCACAUUUGUGAUAUGUUGAAAAGCAUCUCUCUUGGCAACCAAUCUAUGUUUGAGGAAGAUUGGGUAAUGCUGAUGUGUUCCAUUCAUGAAACUGUAUUUGAUACAUAAUCCUAUUAUUAAUUCGUAUGCUUAGUCAACCUAGGAAAUCAAAAUAAUGUUUUGAAGUUCUUAUUUGAGCAAUAUGGCCUUGACUUGGAGGGUAGUUUUAGUUGUUUUGUUUUUAAGUGACUGUGGUUUAAAGCACAAAUGCCCCAAGGUGGGGAGACUUCUCUCUGUGAUUAUUGUUGCUAUUAAAUUCUGAACUGUAUCCAUAUUUUAAGGAAGGAGCUAAAAAUGGAAAUUCAUGAAACAUAAAUGGUAUCAAGAACUUUAUCAGUAUGCUUUGUUGAAAGCAGAAAUUAAGAUAAUAAUUGAGUUCAAUUCGCCUCUCCGCAUUGCCUAUUGAUACACUUUACUAAUCAUGAAAUUCUAACCUAAAAGGAAAACAUUUUCCUGCUUGUCUUAGAAGAAAGUGGAAUAAUUCCACUGAUUGUGAUAAUGGUUUCAAUUUCUACACAAUAUAAAUAUCCAGUAUAAAGGAAAGCGUUAAGUCGGUAAGCUAGAGGAUUGUAAAUAUCUUUUAUGUCCUCUAGAUAAAACACCCGAUUAACAGAUGUUAAACCUUUUAAUGUUUUGAUUUGCUUUAAAAAUGGCCUUCCUACACAUUAGCUCCAGCUAAAAAGACACAUUGGAGAGCUUAGAGGAUAAGUCUCUGGAGCAGAAUUUAUCACACACAAAAGUUACACCAACAGAAUACCAAGCAGAAUGAUGAGGACCUGUAAAAUACCUUGUGCCCUAUUAAAAAAAAAAAAAAAAAAAAAGCCAGUAACUGAAUCCAUUUUGAUUUUUGGUUGAGUUUCCUACACAAAGAAGAAAAUAACUGAGAAUCUGGAAUGUUGUAGUCCAUCCUUUAAAGAGUAAGAAAGUAGCAGUUAAUGCUAGUAACCGUGAAUUAGGCACCACUGAAAGCACAUCCCGAAUUUCUUUAACAACAACAUUUUAUAGUGAACACUACAAGUUUUUAUAUUUAAAAAUUAAGACUCUGUAUAUCCUUAAGGUGCUCUAUGCUUUACCAGUAAUUCACAGGGUAUUUCAAAUGGUAGAAUCAUUUUAGCUUCUGUGCUUCCUUUUUCUAAAUAAUGCAACUUGUAAGAGUUGACAUUGUAAUAAGCUUUAUAAUAGUAUAACCGUCAGGAGAUAUAUAUAUAUAUAUAUACACAUACACACACACACACACAUAUAUACUAUACAUAUAUAAAAUGGGGAUAUUACUAUUGUAUGAUUAAAUCAUUCUUAAGUCCCCAAGGAAAAAAAAUCAUAAACAAAUAGAAAGAACUAAACAGAAAAGAAAGAAAGAAAAGAUCCCUUUGCUAUGAGCUCGCUGUAUAUUGAUAAGUGUAAGAAUUGUGUUGCAUGAAUAACCGCUUUGGGCUGGAUUUGAAGUAUUUUGAUGUUGUGUUUUGCAAAUAUUGAAGUUACAAUAAUGGCAACAGAAAAGGAACAGAUACACAGCUUUACACUUAGCAGAAUGUUACAUUUAAAAUCUGACAAGGCGCCAAGAUGGUGACUGUCUCCUCUAAACCACGAAAGAGUAAGAUUUGUGCAACCCUCCUCCUCUUCCACCUCCUUCAGGAGAAUUAAAUGAAUCAAGACUUUGGAAAGACGGGGAAGAGCCGGGACUUGGCAGUACUUGAAACAGGAGGAAUACACCAGCCUAAAUGUACAGACUUUGUAGCCGAGCCCACUCGAUCGGUCUGUGCCUUCACGUGACCACCAUCUGUGCCUCCCUCGCUCCAUCCAAAUUUGUGUAGGCUGCUCCUUGGAGCUAUGCCUAAAAUAUAGCUACACCAGAGCCCUGGAAACUGUAGUCAAGUAACAGGCCUCACUGUUUUUUUUCUUUGGAUUAAAAGUGUAUAUCUCUCUACUGAGGGGUUUCCAGCUUUACACUUCUAUAGGUUGUUCUGACAGUGAGAACACAUUAUGUACAUGUUUUCUAUUCAUGUCCAGGGCAUGAGAAUCUUAAUAUUCUUAUACUUCCCUUUUUGCAUGCAGUAUGUCUGGAAUAUGUUUAUAAAAUUUUAGCAAGGGGUGAGAUCAAGGGACAAAGGUAGAGUGGUUAUUUAAAGACAAUCAGAAAUGAACUUAAAAGCUGCCCUGCAAAACCAAUCCUUUCCUAUCAUGAAGAGUACCUUCAUAUUUUCUAGAGAUUGUCUCUGAACCGUUGCUACAUAGCCAUAAAUUUCUGUAAAUCAUGUUGGCUAUCAGUUCUUGCUAUUCUCAGAGCACUCUAUCAUGUUUUUAGGUGUAUAUUGUGUAUUCAGGAUAGCAUUAAAAAGAACUGAUGGCAAAUGUAUUGACUCACAGUGGAAACAUUCAUUUGGAUGAAGAAUUAGUGGUUUAGCCUUUGAAAUGAAUACCUUGAAUCAUUUCUUCUGAUUUUCUAGUAGUUUAUUAUCUCAAAUGAUUAUUAUCCCCUUCAAAAAUACUGGUCUGUACUUUGGUGUUGUGGAUUCAUUUUUCUGGCAUUGAUCAAAUAGCAAAUACAAAAUAAAGCAUUUCUACAUGUUUGAGGUGGUUGUUUUUAAAGGGGAUAUGUGUAAUGCAGAUUUUCUUUAUUAAUAAAAUUUUCAUAAUCUCUGAAAA